AGGAAGUGGUGAGUUCGGAGUAGAGAUGGCCGCGCUUGCACCGCUGCCCCCGCUCCCCGCACAGUUCAAGAGCAUACAGCAUCAUCUGAGGACGGCUCAGGAGCAUGACAAGCGAGACCCUGUGGUGGCUUAUUACUGUCGUUUAUACGCAAUGCAGACUGGAAUGAAGAUCGAUAGUAAAACUCCUGAAUGUCGCAAAUUUUUAUCAAAGUUAAUGGAUCAGUUAGAAGCUCUAAAGAAGCAGUUGGGUGAUAAUGAAGCUAUUACUCAAGAAAUAGUGGGCUGUGCCCAUUUGGAGAAUUAUGCUUUGAAAAUGUUUUUGUAUGCAGACAAUGAAGAUCGUGCUGGACGAUUUCACAAAAACAUGAUCAAGUCCUUCUAUACUGCAAGUCUUUUGAUAGAUGUCAUAACAGUAUUUGGAGAACUCACUGAUGAAAAUGUGAAACACAGGAAGUAUGCCAGAUGGAAGGCAACAUACAUCCAUAAUUGUUUAAAGAAUGGGGAGACUCCUCAAGCAGGCCCUGUUGGAAUUGAAGAAGAUAAUGAUAUUGAAGAAAAUGAAGAUGCUGGAGCAGCCUCUCUGCCCACUCAGCCAACUCAGCCAUCAUCAUCUUCAACUUAUGACCCAAGCAACAUGCCAUCAGGCAACUAUACUGGAAUACAGAUUCCUCCGGGUGCACACGCUCCAGCUAAUACACCAGCAGAAGUGCCUCACAGCACAGGUGUAGCAAGUAAUACUAUCCAACCUACUCCACAGACUAUACCUGCCAUUGAUCCCGCACUUUUCAAUACAAUUUCCCAGGGGGAUGUUCGUCUAACCCCAGAAGACUUUGCUAGAGCUCAGAAGUACUGCAAAUAUGCUGGCAGUGCUUUGCAGUAUGAAGAUGUAAGCACUGCUGUCCAGAAUCUACAAAAGGCUCUCAAGUUACUGACGACAGGCAGAGAAUGAAGCCUUUGUAUGACAGACCCAUGUAUUUUUGGCAUGAGGAACUAACAGUCCAUUACUCUAUCUUCAGCCUAUCAGGAUCACAGUUUUAAGGAAGACUUGGUUUUGUUGAAUAUGACAAUGAAAUCUGUGUGUAUCAGAUUUUUAUUGAAGCAUUCAUCAGCAGCCUCAACCAGUUUUCAUUGUCCAUUUACUAGAUUCAAUCGUCUCUGAGUAUAUAGGGCUGAUGUUAGCAAGACCCUAAAAAUGUCCAUUGAACCCUGCUUCAAAAAAUGAAAACACACCUCUAUAAAAUGUGUACUGGGAAUAAGCUUUGUAUUUACAUACAUUAGGGGAAUUUUUUAAAAUCUGUAAUGUUUGGACAAACAGAUGAUAUUACUUUGCUAUAAAAUUAUAAAUGUAACUUUUAAUAAAGAUAGCCAGAAUAUUCUAAAUUAGAAAUUACGUUUUUGUUUCCCUCAAGACAUAAAACAAAUAUAAACAUUCUAAACUGCUGGAUGAAUCUGAAAAGACAUUAAGUUCAAAUUUUAAUUUAUUCUCAUAUUAAAUAUAACUCCAUUAAAAGUUUAAAAUUUCAUGGGAGAAAAUAUAAUAAGGUAAAGAGGUAGAAUCACUUUCAGACUUAAGAAUAAUGUUGAUUUCCCAAGUGCUUUACCUUAUCUGUUAAAGCGUAAGAUGAAUUGGUAUUUGCUUCAUAGGCAGUUUGACUGCAUGUAUUAGAGAAUGAAAAGAAGAUAUUUGUAGUAAUGCCUGGAAACUUGGUGCUUUAAAUUAAGGUACUCCUCUGCUGCUGUAGAAUGGAUUCCACACAGUGGAUAGCUAUGGGUGAUUCAGAAUAUUAUGUUUAGAUUCCCAUUUGUUAAGUUUAUAAGUUUUGUGGGGAAUUAUGAACUUACUGUGUACUACCUGCAUUUGUGCUGUGUGAAAAAUAAAUACAAGGAUUCGUUUAGCUAAUUCAACUUACUACAAAGACAAAUGUCUGUUUUUAUUUGCCUGCUAGGAUUGUCUUUUUUAAAAGUCAUUUUUAUUUAUAGGAAUAUGGGUGUUUCUAUAGGAAGAAACAGGUUUUUUGUUUUUUGUUUUUUAAGAUAAAUUUGACAAAGUUAACUGAAAUUUAUCUGGUCCAUUUUAUUCAUGCUACUAAGAUGGGAAUCUUUAAACACAAGGGUCAGCAAGCUUUGGCCCAUGGAUUGGCCACCUGUUACGUAAAUAAAGUUUCUUUGAAACAAGCCUACACUCAUUCAUUUAUGUUUUGUCUGUGGUUGCUUUCCACAACUGCAGAGUUGUAUGGCUUGCAAGUCUAAAAACAUUUACUAUUUGGCCCUCUAAGAAAAAGUUAAGACACCUAGUCUAAUGGCCUUUUGGGAAAAAACAAAUCACUAACUCAUAAUCAUUUAUAUCCAUUAUUUUCUGCAUAAAUGUAAUGCUAUUGUACAGGGUUUGGUAGAAUAAAUAUUCAGACUGACUAAACUGUUCUAAAUCCUCACAAAAAAGUCCCCAAACAACAUGCCUCCUAAAAAACAUUUUCCUAUCUUUUACAAGAGGUAUGAACAUUUGUAGGGUUCCACAUUUGCAUCUAGAAAUCCAAUGCUCUUUAGAAUGUUAUUACGAAUAGAAAGAUGGCCAGGAUGACCUUUAGUGUUACAUGAUGUUCAGCAAAUUUUAAUUCAAACCUUGAUAUGCCUGGACACUGAAAAGUAAACGCAUCACCUCCUAUUUUAUACCCUACCUUCUGGUUCCCAAUUGGGAGAGCACAUAGAGGGAAGGAGACAAUAUAGAAACUACGGAGUCCGCUGGUAGUGGGCUGCAUGGUGUGACAGAGCCCUUCUCUGUAAAAUGGAAAUGACACCACUAGCCAUCUCAAUAGUUACAAGAAUUAAAAGAGAUACAGUACCUGAAGUGCUUAGCGCAUGGUAGCAUUUCAUAAAUGUUUAGUGUCAAUACUAAUGCUCUAAUAAUGUAAAUUGUUAAUAAUUUAUUUCCCUAAUAUCAGGAAAUCCCAGUUGUCUAUGUGGCCCAGUGCUUAAAAACGCCUUCUUGCAUGAGGGGAUUGAACUAUACAAUGUUUGUUAACUUUGUAUUUGUAUUUUUUCCUAUAAAAUCUUAAAAUAAAAUUAGGAGAUGUGUUCUGAUGUAACAGUAGGAUUAGCAAUUUUCAUUUAUUCCUUCCAUAUAUAUUUACUGAAUGGCUACUAUAUGCCUGGUAUUGUUCUUUGAAAGCAGAAACAGCAGGAAAAAAAGUCCCUCCCUCAUAGAGUUUACAUUCUAAAAGGGAGGAAAUAGAUAAUAAAAUAUACAUUACAUUUAAUCAGUGGCUCUCCGAGUGUGAUUAGAAAUACAAAUUUUGGGCCCCACCUGUCCUACCCAAUCAGAAACUCUAGGGAUGGGUCCCAGCCUUCUGAGUUUUAAGAGACACUUAAGGUGGUCCCUAAAGUUCGAGUGGUUUAGCUCUACCCAAAUCAGAAAUAUUGCAAGUCUGAGAAAAGAGAUUCUCCUCAAACCGGUUCUCAAAGGUGUCUCUGGACGACCGGCAUCAGCAUCACCUGCGAACUUGCUAGAAAGUUCUGGGGACCACACUAUGGGAACUUCUGUAUUAAAUAGUGAUAAAUGCUAUGGAGGAAACAUUGAGGACAGGAUAGGAGAUGCUUAGGUGUGUACAGACAUAUGCAUAUUUCAAUAGAAUAGCCAGGAUAGACCUCCCUGAGGUAACAUUUGAGCAAAGAAGGAAAAGAGUAACUAGUAUGCAGAUACAUACAUGGAGGAAGAGCAUUCCCAACAGGUAGACAGAAAUCAGGUCAGAGGGUAAAAGCAGGAGAAAGGCUGGUGAGGGAGCUAAAAGCUUAGGAUCAUAAAGCUUUUUUGUAAGACACUUGACUGGGAGCUAUAUGGAAAGGUUUUCAGAAGAAACGUAGCCUGAUGUGACUUAACUUUUGAAAUAAUCAUAUUGGCUCCUAUGUUGAGAAUAGACCGUAAGGUGGGUGGUAAGUAAGGGAGGAAGCUGGGAGACCAGUUAAAAAGAGUAUUAACAAUAGGCCGGGGGCGGUGGUUCGCACCUGCAAUCCCAGCACUUUGGGAGCCAAGGCAGGCGGAUCAUCUGAGGUCAGGAGUAUAUAUUUAUUAAUAUAUAAAUAUGUAUUUAUAUAUAAAUCAUAAAUAUAUUAAUAAAUAUAUAAUAUAUAUAUUAGCCUGGCAUGGUGGCACAUACCUCUAAUCUCAGCUACUGAAGAGGCUGAGGCAGGAGAAUCGCUUGAACCCAGGAGGCGGAGGUUGCAGUGAGCCGAGAUCGUGCCACUGCACUCCAGCCUGGGCGACAGAGCGAGACUCCUUCUCAAAAAAAAAAAAAGUAUUACAAUAAUCAAGGUGAGAUAUUAUGAUGUCUUAGUCCAGGAGUAGCCUUGGAGGUAAUAAAACGGGAUUGGUUUCUGGCGGCUUUUUUUUAGGUAGAGCCACAGGAUUUCUGUAAACUGGAUGUGAGGUACGAACAUAAGAGAAGGAGUAAAGGUUGACUCCAGAUUUUUCACCUGAAUGCCUGAAAGGAAUGAGUAAUCAUGUACUGCAGUAGGGAAAGUUGCCGAAUUCCUCUCUCACUUAGACUGAAGUACAAUGUUUCCAAGUUUUUGUGACCAGCCCAAGUGAAACUGAUAACGGUGUUUUGUCAAUGCGGCAGAGGGAGAAGAAGAAAUAAGGUUCUGCUGACAAUGAUUGCCACAGAUAUCUCACCAAAUCACUGCUGAACUGGAGCUGCAAGCCAAGAAUAGUUCCCAUGGUUAGCAUGGCCUAGGAAGUUUACUGACAUCAGGACUACACCAAGAAAAAGACUCCAGUUAUGGGUCUUGAAAAUUAAUAUCCUCAGAUGUUUUUAGAAUUUAUAUAUGACUUGUAAUUCUAGAAAUUUGAGAAUUCUAUGUAUGCAUUGAAAGAUUAUAUACUGUCUUUUCUAAAGAAACACCCUAAUAGCAGCAUUGUACAAAUAUUUUCAACUCUAAAAGAAUAAUAGCUAAUGGAGUUGAUGGGUUUUGGUUUUCAUAUGAGAAGUAUCCUUCCCUGGUUGGUUGUAAUCUUUGAAGUCUAUGUGGAAUUCUAAGACUGCAGGCUUGUUCAUUGGAGUACACUUAAGUAGGACAAAUUCUAAGUAAGCAACACUUCAAUAAUAAUCAUAAUAGCUAACAUUUCAAUGUUUACUAAAUGUCAGAUACUAUUCUAAGUAUUUUGCAUAUAUUAAUUCAUUUAAUCUUCACAGUGGUCCUGAGAGGUAGGCUUUAUUUCUGUUUUAAGAUGAGGAAAGGGAGCCACAGAGUAACAAAUUUGCCUAAGGUAACACAGCUAAUAUUUAUUUCUAAGCUCAGACUGCCUGUUUCAGAUCAUAAGAAGUAUCAUCCAUGUCAGUAAGUCACCUGUUACAUUGUAAGUACAAUGAGAUGUUAUGAGUUCCACAUUAUCAAGGUCAUUGGACAGUUCCUUUUAUUAGUGAGGUGUUAGCACCUAAAUUUUUCUAUUAUCUGGGCCAUAUGUUCCAAUUGACAGUGCUAGGCAGUGAACACAGGGUAUGAACUUGAAAAUCUGAUUGCACCCUCAAUAUCUGGAAUAUACACUGAUCUAUGACCUGAAAUUGUAUGGACUGCAGCAAUCCAAGGGGACACUAAGCAGGGUUUGAGUAAUGCUACAAUGGAUUUAUAGGUCAUUUUGGAGAAGGUGUUCCACAUCAUUAGGGAGUCUGGGUUUCCCAGAUGUGCCUGUUUUAUCCUUUUUAUUUUAAAUAACAUCACUGUCUUUCCUAACUAAAAAUUCUUCAUCUUCAGGAAAUAAGAUUGAGAUACGGACUGAAAAUAUAAAAUUAGCAAUAAUGUUUAUUAUUAGAUACUUCCUCAAUUAAAUUUCUCCCUGAAAGUCUUAGGCAAAAGCCCCUGUCUCUUACUUCAUAUAUCAAGUUUGGAGGGAAAGACAUAAUUGCAUAGCAGUAUUCCAUGAAUAUAACUUAAUGGGGAACUGGCUUCAGAGUUCAGCAAUAUUGGGAAGUCUUGUCAAAUAUUAAGUCAUUCAUAUGUUCAAAAAUAUUAAUAUGUAUUGAGCAUCUACCAUCAAAUAUUUAAUAUGAUAAUGCCAUACUGGAUAUUAUAUACGAGUUACAAUAAUUCUUCCUAAAGUCAGGGAAAGCUUCACAGAUAAGGUUGAGCUGAAGGUUUGGCAGGCAGGGAAGCAAGGAGAAGUUAGCAGAGAGAAAAGCACAAGCAACACCAUGGAGGAACAAAUGUGGGCAAUUCAGGUAACUCGAGUAAUUUAGUGUUACUAUGCAUAUGGCCUAUGGAGGCCAGGAGUGUAAAUGUAUUAUGGCUGGGGCGGGGGGCUAGGGAAUGUGUUAUGACUAAAUUGUAUCCCUUCAGAAUUCAUAUUUUGAAGCACUGAUCUCCAGUGUGUCUGUGUUCAGAGGCAGGUCCCAUAGGGAGGCAAUUAAGGUUACAUGAGAUCAUAAAGGUGAGGCCCUAAUCCUAUAGGUCUGCUGUCAUUACAAGAAGAGGAAGAGCCACCGGAGCUGGCUCAUUCUGCACGUGUACAGAGAAGAGGCCAUGUGAGGACACGCAGAGGCUCGAAUAUGCUCUCAACCCUAUCAGUUGCCUGCUUUAAUUCAUCCCAUGGAAUUGUUUUGUCUUUUCGACCCCUCGGCUAUGUUAUUUGUAUUGUGAUAUAGGGGAUAUUCGGAGUCCUCUGAGACGGGACAAGGACACUGGACGGUCUAUUGUGCCAUGCUUAUAUAUUUUCUGUAUACAAUGCUUUCUGUAUAAAACCAGUAAUACCUGAGAAACAACAGUAACUUGACAAAAUUACUAUUGAUCACUUAACUUUAUGUAUCACGUAAGUUAAACUUUAUUUAUUUACAUGUGUCUCCCUCAUUAGAUGCUAAGUUCCUUGAUAUUUUAUACAUUUGUGAAUUCCUGGUAAUUCACAUGAAGCUUGAUGCAUUGUAAGUAUUCUGACCUGGUGAAAUAAAUAUACGAAUGGGCAAAAAAAUAUAUACUAAAAUGAUCAAAUAAAGGUUGUGUUCAGAAA